GUCAUCGCCACCGGCCUCGGGGACCUGCCUCACGGAAGUGGCUCGCGCGUCCAAGAGGGGAGGCCUGGUGUGGGGACGCUCAGGUGCCGGCGUGGGGCCCCCUCGGAGGCUGUGAAUCUUUUGGACCCCCGAAUGUAAAUGGGAGAUGGUAGGGGCCGGUCCGGGGGCGAGAGGUGUCUGGCUGGGGAACGUUGACCCACACCAGGUCCCGUACAGGAACGGAGACUCCCUAGGACCGUGAGAGCCAGCUUCGUAAUUCUCUUGCUCUUCAAACCUGAGAGUAGGGUGUUGCUCCGUUACCUUCCAUUCGUGUGCAGGAGAGAGUUAAGUAAAUCAAUAAAGAAGGUAUCAGCAAGUGAGAAAUGCCCCCCAAAGACCGGAUGAGAGAGUACCCAGAGAAGGAGAAGCCAGCAAAGGAGACGACACAGACAAGACCUCAGAGAUCAAAGGAAGAGGCCCCUUAAUAUCCUGGAAUAAUGGGACCCAUCCCCGUAAUCAGUGAAUCUCAUCCACCCGCUUGCCAGCUUCUACCCGCAGCAAGUAGAAGCUAAGUCCUGGCUCAAAUCUCUUCCCUCCCUCCCUCUCCCAGCUGUCAGUGCUUUUGGACUUGUGCUCAGAUACAAUCCCUGCCCUUCAGGAAUUCAGACUCAGAGAAGAAAAAACAGAGUGAAAGAAAUGCAGAACUAUCUGCUGGCCAUGAUAGAAGCAAGGAAAAGGUUGCUUUGGAAAAGCUUAAUAGCAAGUAGGUGUCUGUUUGAUGGUGUGGGGUGGCUAGCAGAAAGGAGACAUUGUAGGCAGAGGAAGACUCAGCCAAGACAGACAGAAGUAUGACAUGGCAAGGCACCUUAGAGCAGUAGCUCCCAAACUUCAGAGUCCACAUCACAGUUUUUGCUGUUUACCUAUAUUUUAAACUAGCUUAAAAAGUUUUCUAAUUCAUUUCUUUAAAGGAAGCUGUAUAUCACAUAAAAUCUAAAUCACUCAAAAUUAUGGGUUUGAUGGGCUUUUCUAAUAUACAGUUUGUAUUGUAUAUCUAAGAUCACCUCCCCAACCAAUCUUUGGGACACUUGGCAUUAGGGGACACAUCUCUUAACUAUGACCAGAGGCCACAACACACUGGCAGCAACAUCUGUCAGCCUUUUCUUAGUGGCACAGGCCUGCACAUCACAGAGGCUUGGAAAUGAUCCUCACCUCCACACAUGUAUAUCCCUGUGUUAUAACAGGGCGUGAUUUUUAAGAAAAGAGACCAGCUUCUAGUCCCAUUUCUUUCCAGGCACACCUCAUAUCUUCUGUCUUUCUUCAUUCUGGGAUUUGGGGGUUAGGGAGAUGAAAAGGAGUAAAGAAUUGGAAGAAAUGUCGGUCUCAGAAUAAAGAUUAUAGAAGGUUAACUUUUAAAAAUCUACAUGGAUAGACUUCGUGACCAGCUGAGACCGCAGUUGAAUUGUGGUCCUCUAAACUACUGAAUAUUCCUGAUGUAUUGCUGGUGAAGUAGUAUUUGAAGCUUUUCAUCAGUUGGCUCAUUCUUUACUCAAGAAUAAACCUCAAGAAACGUCAUCAGGGUCAGAAUGACAACGGCAACACGACAAGAAGUCCUUGGCCUCUACCGCAGCAUUUUCAGGCUUGCGAGGAAAUGGCAGGCGACAUCAGGGCAGAUGGAAGACACCAUCAAAGAAAAACAGUACAUACUAAAUGAAGCCAGAACGCUGUUCCGGAAAAACAAAAAUGUCUCAAGCCAGCCACUCACGGACACAGACCUAAUUAAACAGUGUAUAGAUGAAUGCACAGCCAGGAUUGAAAUUGGACUGCAUUACAAGAUUCCUUACCCAAGGCCAAUUCAUCUGCCUCCAAUGGGCCUUACCCCACUCCGAGGCCGGGGACUUCGAAGCCAAGAGAAACUGAGGAAACUUUCCAAACCAGUAUAUCUCAGAUCUCAUGAUGAAGUUUCCUAAUCUAGAGGAAAGUUUAUUUCUGCAAAUGAUGAGCCAACUAGUUAUUGAAUGUAAACCAGAUGGCAAAACACUUCUUGAUUAGGGGCAAAAAUUCAAAUGUCUUCUUAAAACCUCCACAAUUGAUUCUCCCCCUGUGAUGUAAACUUAGAUAUCCCUAGAGUUUCUCAGCAUCUUUCUUCCUGAGUGGAUGGCAUUAUCCCUAGAGGUCAUGGACCUUACAUCCUCACUGCAGUCACCUUUGGAAACAAGACCGAGGCCUGUAGAAGGAAAGCGGAAGGAUGUAAGAGCUGUUCAUGGGAAUUCCAUUCACCACACAUGCCAGCUGAUGCAAAGAAAUUUGCCAGUCACUGGAAGUUACUGUGGCUACUAUAAAACUAUGUACCACUCUCAGAAUAUUCUUAGGCUUUUUUUUUUUCAAGUUAUAGAUUUGCUUAAAGUGAGGUUUUUUGGUGUGUGCUUUUUUGUUGUCUUUUGACCCUUCCAGUUUCCAGACAAACUUGUCUUAAAAAGUGCAUCAUUGGAUUGACCAUGGUUUUUCAUGAAAUUUUAUGAGAUUUCUGCCUUAACAAAAUGCAUAUAUUCCUUAUCUUAAAGCCUGUCAUUACUUAGGAUGCACUUAUAGGAUCUGAAAAGCUCACUUUAAACUCAUACUACAUUCGUUACGAGUAUUUUACGUUAACAUAAUUGAAAAGUACAAGGUCCAAGCUGGCUUUCAAAUUAUGUCUAAACAGAAAUGGGACAAAUAGACUUGAAAAUAGAAGGGAUUUAUUCCACCCCUGCAAGGGUAGAGUCAGGUGAGAGUCCCUUGGUGAGUCAUUUGUACAUCAGUGUCAUUUCUUCUUAACCUCUGAAGAAGAUGGGCAUCAGAAAUAAAGACAAAGCACUAUCAA